AGACUACUGCUACUUACAGCACCGUAUAGCAGCCCUGCUCCUACAUUUUGCUGCCUUACUCUGCCCCGAAUGCACUGGAGUGGGGAUGGUCCAUCGGCAACUAUAAACUGAUUCUCAUCAGGAAACUGCACAUUAUCUCCCCAUCACUUCAAAGGUCUCGUCAGGCAGAGGUGACGCCAGGAGAUGAUUUAAAGGUGAAAAUGACAAGGUUUCCACCCCUCAAACCUUGGCUCCUUUUCUGACAAUACAGUCUGAAUGAACCCGAUGUCUUUUUUUUUACUGUGGAAAUAGGAUCGGAAGAGAGUAACAUUUUUUUUUUUUUAAUCCUGAUAAAGAAGAUUGUUGGGAAGCUCUUUGAAAAAAAAUUUUAAAUUGUGGCACAGAUGGAUUUUAAAAAGUGUUAGAUCUUUCCAAUGAACACUAAUAGAGUACUCUGCUCUUGGCUGGAUUUUUCAGAAUUAAGAAAAAAAUGAAUGUAUGAUCAUCUGAAAAGGGCUUUCUCUCAAUCCCACUUCAUGGCAUGACCUCUGCUGGAUCAUUAGUUCUAGCCAGAGAAGUAGCAAAGGAACAUGACGUCUGAGACCUCCCUUCCCUCAUCAGUGGGGCUGACUGAGCUGGGGGCUUGAAGCCGGAGGUAACCUUUCCUGUCGAAUGUUCUCUUUAGAGAAUGGCAAUGGUCUCUGCGAUGUCCUGGGUCCUGUAUUUGUGGAUAAGUGCUUGUGCAAUGCUACUCUGCCAUGGAUCCCUUCAGCACACUUUCCAGCAGCAUCACCUGCACAGACCAGAAGGAGGGACGUGUGAAGUGAUAGCAGCACACCGAUGUUGUAACAAGAAUCGCAUUGAGGAGCGGUCACAAACAGUAAAGUGUUCCUGUCUACCUGGAAAAGUGGCUGGAACAACAAGAAACCGGCCUUCUUGCGUCGAUGCCUCCAUAGUGAUUGGGAAAUGGUGGUGUGAGAUGGAGCCUUGCCUAGAAGGAGAAGAAUGUAAGACACUCCCUGACAAUUCUGGAUGGAUGUGCGCAACAGGCAACAAAAUUAAGACCACGAGAAUUCACCCAAGAACCUAACAGAAGCAUUUGUGGUAGUAAAGGAAAACCAACCCUCUGGAAAAUACAUUUUGAGAAUCUCAAACAUCUCACAUAUAUACAAGCCAAAUGGAUUUCUUACUUGCACUUUGACUGGCUACCAGAUAAUCACAGUGCGUUUACUGUGUGUAACGAAAUAUCCUACAGUGAGAAGACACAGCGUUUUGGCAACACCAUGGAAAGUGGGCUUAAAAAAGGGUUUUCUCAGUGAAAUUUUUGGGCAUCAUGAAGAACGAUCAACUAUCUUCUAAUUUGAAUCUAUAGUUACUUUGUACCAUUUGAAAUAUAUGUAUAUAUAUAUAUAUAAUAUUUUGAAAUAUUAUCUAUUCUCUUCAAGAAAUGAACAGUACCACAGUUUGAGACGGCUGGUGUACCCCUUUGAGUUUUGGAUGUUUUGUCUGUUUUGCUUUGUUUUGUUAGUCAUUUCUUUUUCUAACGGCAAGGAAGAUAUGUGCCCUUUUGAGAAUUCAAGAUGGCACUGACACGGGAAGGCCAGCUACAGGUGGACUCCUGGAAUUUGAGGCAUCAUAAUGAUACUGAAUCAAGAACUUCCUUCUGCUUCUACCAGAUGGCCCAAGGAAGCACAUCGUCCUGUUUUAUUGCUUUCUACCCUGUGCAAUAUUAGCAUGCAAGCUUGGCUUACAUAGUCAUACUUUAUAUUCAAUUGAUAUAUAAUAACCGUUCUAACCUCUUCCAGGAAAAUAUUUUUAGAACUACUAGCUUUUCCACUUAGAAGAAAAUGAGGAUUCUUAAGGGAGCCACUCCACCAUGCUAUUAAGACUCUGGCAGAGUUAUGGGUAGGAUAUGGAUCCCUACAUGAAUAAGUCCUGUAAAUACAAUGUCUUAAGGCUUUGUAUAGCUGUCCUAGACUGCAGAAAUGUCCUCUGAUUAAAUCCAAAGUCUGGCAUCGUUAACUACAUAGUGCUGUAGCAACAAGUCUUAUCAUGGCAUCUCUUUCUAUGUUUGGUUUGCUUUUUCCAAGAGUAUUCAGGUCUCCUCUUGUGAGAUAGGAAGGCCAUGAAAACAAUUAGAUUUCAAGAUGAUCUAUGUGACCAAAUGUUGGACAGCCCUAUUAAAGUGGUAAACAACUUCUUUCUAAA